AAGUGCAGGGACGGAGGCCGAAGCGGAGCGGUCUAGGGAGCCGCGGCCGCGGGUCACCCGGCGGGUAGCAGUUGCUGAGUGUCAGCUAGACAGCAGCGACUAGGGCUCGGGCGCCGGCGAGAUGCCUUUGUUCACCGCCAACCCCUUCGAGCAAGACGUGGAAAAAGCCACGAAUGAGUACAACACUACAGAAGAUUGGAGUCUUAUUAUGGACAUAUGUGACAAAGUUGGAAGUACUCCUAAUGGAGCGAAAGAUUGCCUAAAAGCCAUAAUGAAAAGGGUAAAUCAUAAGGUUCCACAUGUUGCUCUGCAAGCACUAACUCUUCUUGGGGCUUGUGUGGCAAACUGUGGAAAGAUAUUUCAUUUAGAAGUAUGUUCCCGUGAUUUUGCAACAGAAGUACGUGCUGUGAUUAAAAAUAAGGCACAUCCUAAAGUAUGUGAAAAACUGAAAUCUUUAAUGGUGGAGUGGUCAGAAGAAUUUCAGAAGGACCCUCAGUUUAGUCUGAUAUCUGCAACUAUUAAAUCUAUGAAAGAAGAAGGAAUUACUUUUCCUCCAGCAGGUUCUCAGACUGUCUCAGCUGCUGCCAAGAAUGGUACGUCAUCGAACAAAAACAAAGAGGAUGAAGACAUAGCUAAAGCUAUUGAAUUAUCGCUGCAAGAACAGAAACAGCAACACACAGAAACAAAAUCCUUAUAUCCAUCUUCAGAAAUUCAGUUAAAUAAUAAGGUUGCACGGAAAGUGAGAGCUUUAUAUGAUUUUGAAGCUGUUGAGGACAAUGAACUCACCUUUAAACAUGGUGAAAUAAUUAUUGUUUUGGAUGACAGUGAUGCCAAUUGGUGGAAAGGAGAAAAUCACAGAGGAAUAGGACUUUUCCCAUCCAAUUUUGUAACAACUAAUUUAAACAUAGAGACUGAGGCAGCGGCUGUGGACAAAUUGAAUGUAAUUGAUGAUGAUGUGGAGGAAAUUAAGAAAUCAGAGCCUGAGCCUGUUUAUAUAGAUGAGGAUAAGAUGGAUAGAGCCCUGCAGGUACUUCAGAGUAUAGAUCCAACAGAUUCAAAACCAGACUCCCAAGACCUUUUGGAUUUAGAAGAUAUCUGCCAACAGAUGGGUCCAAUGAUAGAUGAAAAACUUGAAGAAAUUGAUAGGAAGCAUUCAGAAUUGUCUGAAUUGAAUGUUAAAGUCCUGGAAGCUCUGGAACUAUAUAACAAAUUGGUGAAUGAAGCACCAGUGUACUCAGUCUAUUCAAAGCUCCACCCUCCAGCACAUUACCCACCUGCAUCAUCUGGGGUUCCAAUGCAGACAUAUCCAGUUCAAUCACAUGGUGGAAACUAUAUGGGUCAGAGCAUUCACCAAGUAACUGUUGCCCAAAGCUAUAGCCUAGGACCCGAUCAAAUUGGUCCACUGAGAUCUCUGCCUCCAAAUGUGAAUUCCUCAGUGACAGCACAGCCUGCUCAAACUUCAUAUUUAAGCACUGGACAAGACACUGUUUCCAAUCCUACUUAUAUGAACCAGAACUCUAACCUACAGUCAGCUACUGGUACAACUGCUUACACACAGCAAAUGGGGAUGUCUGUGGAUAUGUCAUCUUAUCAGAACACUACUUCCAAUUUGCCUCAACUGGCAGGCUUUCCGGUGACAGUUCCAGCUCAUCCAGUUGCACAGCAGCACACAAAUUACCAUCAGCAGCCUCUCCUUUAGAAACAAAUCAAGCAUUUUCUUGAAAGCCUUCAUAAGUGUAUUAUUCAGUCCUUGUGAUACCAACCUGAAAAUAUUAAAACUUUUUUCCCUCUCAACUCAAAAGGACCAUGAAUAAAUAAAGCACAAAAACCUCUCUUAUUCUACAAGGCCAUAAAAGGUUUUUUUUUUUUUUUUUUUUCAGUCCAGUUUGUUUGAAGUCAAUCUUUUCAUCAGAGGCAGCUUAAAGAUGCUUUCAGUUAGUUUUGUCUUACUUUCAGAUUUCUCUACAUAAAUCUAGAUACUCAUUAAGUAGCCUUAUGACAAACAGUAUGAGAUACUUAUGACAAACUCGCUCUGUCACCCAGGCUGGAGUGCAGUAGCAUGAUCGACAGAGUGAGUUUGUCAAAAGUAUCUCAUACUUAUAAACAGUAUGAGAUAGGAGGAUUAAAAUAUUAUUUUAAAGAAACCACUGUUUCCCCCUAAAAUGUCAUAAGAGCACUGAAGAACUUGAAAUAUUUUUUUCAGAGUUUCUCACACACUUUAAAAGUCUAACUUUUUUGUGUGUAAGCAUUUAGCUUGCCAGCAUAUUUCUUUUUGGCUCCUUAAAUUGCGGUUGUGUUUGCAGUAUUGUCACUUUUGCUCUCACUGUUAUGUUGAAUAAUAAUUAGCAUAUAAUUGUCUACAGAAGCAAGAGCAAUCUGGAAGGAACAAAAAUGUUUUCUGUGAUUAACAGUGAAGACCUUGUAAAUGCAGAUGUGUGAUAAAGCAUUUAGUCAGUCCCCCAAACAGUCAUGCCAACUGUGAAGGAAUGUCCCACAAAACAUUUCCAUUCCCUGAGGAAAAACAUUUUCUUUCCUACAUGUAUCUCUGGUAUUUAGAAUUGUCACUAAUAACCUUUUCAAGUGAUUUUGGCUAUUCUCUAAUGAAGAUAUGGUCCAUUUGUUUUUCUUCCUGCAAUGUGGUGUGCAGAGAUGCUGCAUAUCCUUUUUAUGGGAUUGCGUGUGAAUUUGAACCAUGAGACAUUCCUAAUAAUUUGUUGUGAGAUAUACCAAGCAUGGAUGAUAAGUGUGUUUUUAGUGGUGUGUUGUUUUUUUAAAGAGGUGAUUCAAGUACCGUUGCUAAGCUGUCAACAUACCAAGCUGUUGAAAAAAUUGACCAUUUCUUUCAGAAGUAAUUCUCAGCCUGUGGAAUAAUAGCAGGUGAAGACUUCAUAGAAGGCGACAGAUUGAUAGGGAGGCUAUUGAAGCAGUUUUUCUGAAGCCUGCAUUUUGAGUUAGUUUAUAGUGCUAAUAGAUUCUAUAUAACUGUGAGAGUUUGGUAGUAAACCAGUAGGGAUUGUUUUCUCUCCUAAAAAUUUGCACACUACUUCAUUGUCUACCAACUUUUUACAUAUUGGAAAAUAGAAAUUGCAAAUACAUACAUGUAUGGAAACAUAUUCAGAUUGGGAAAAACAAUGGACAUUAGUUUUUAAAAAGUUACGUGGAAGCAAGAUUUCUAUAUUUGUUUUUUUAAAGGAAGCAGUCAUUCUUUCUACUAAAUCCAUUUCAAGCUAGUUCUCUGAAAAUUUUGCCAUUUAUCUACAGAAAUUUGAUUAUAAAUAUGUUCCUUUUUCAAAGAAACUUUAUUCUAGAACAAAAUAGUCUAUAUGGUACUUGAUCUACAUUUAAGUGGAAAAAUUAGCAGUAUUUGAAAGCUCAGUUUAUGUCAUUGUCUUAACUUCAGAUACAAAUAACUGAACAGAAAGUUUUAACCUUUAAUAUCUCAUGUUCUGUUUUUUAUUCAGUAUUUUCCUUUAUGUUAAUUCAAUUAUAUACUUCUGAAUGGCACCUUACUUUUUGGAAACAAAUCUUCUGUUAUUUACAAAAUAAUAAUUUUUAAAAAACAUUUAAAAAAAAUCCAAAGCUGCUCUCGAUAAUAGUCAACAUUUGCAUAUAUAUGGAAUUUCUUACUUUUUUUCUCCCAAACUCUAUUUAAUAAACUUAUUUUAAUGUUUGUGUAUUUCAUGUAUAAUUGUGAUCUCAAUUAUAAAAGUUUAAUUCAGCAUGUCUUUGAGCCAAUAUAAUUACUGCACACCCACUAAAUUGGGAUCAGCCAUUAUAAAUAAUGUAGUUUUAGAAUAAUAAAACAUGACACAUAUAUAUAUAUAUAAAUAUAUAGUAUAUAUUGGCACAUCGGUGAAAGUUUAUAUGUGCAGAAGUUUUUUUCUUUCUCAAGUUAAAAAUUAUUUUUUGCCAUAUGUAAUUUUGUGUUGCAGGCUGUCGAGAGAUAAAAAUGAUUUUAAAUCUGUGUACUGAUGAUUCUUUCGGUGUUAAGAAACACAGGGUUGUGUACUUCCCUUUUUAUGGGCUUAUGGAUUCUAUUUAUAUUAAGACCUGUUUAUAAUUGUUUUCUGCCAAAGGGAAUUGUCUAACUUCAGAUUUCUACAUUGGGUUCAUACUUACUGUUUUAUAUCAGAAAUAAAAAAAUAGCUUCUGCUUUUUCAUAUGAAAUCUUGGUACAUCAGAAAGAAUUCCUGAAAAUUUAUAAUAGAAUGAAUUUUAUUAAUGCAGAAAAAUACCCCAGGGUGUUAAAAUAUAUGAAGUGUGGGAUAUAUUCUUAUAGUUUGUAAAAUGUAGUCAACCAAUACUGUCUUCUAAUUUGGUAAUUUAUUUAUAAAAUUACUUAAACAUUAGGUAAUUAUAUUUGUUAGGAUUUGAAAUUAUUUGUAGUUAAAUUGUCAUGCUGUUUGAAAUAAUUGAUACUUGUCUACGUAAUACAUUUUACUGUAUGUUUUGAAGAUGGUUAUAAUUUCACUUUCAAAAUUUAAAAAAUCAAUUUUAAAUGUUUUAAAAACAUAUAGCUUAGGGAUUUUUUUUAAAAAGGUUUUCUUAGUAAAAACAUAAAUUUAAAAGCCCCUGAGUUCUAGGAGAGGGCUUAUUGAAUUGCUAUAAGAAAGCUGGAGUUACUUUGAUAAGUAAUAAAUUAUAAAUAGCACUGAUCUAUAAUGCUUUAUUUCUAUCGGAAGGUACUUUUUCUUCUUUCAUCAUCAGUUUUAGCCAGUUAGUAAAUGGGAAUACUCAGUUUUAGGGAUUUGAUUUUUGUUUGGUUUAAUUUUCUUUCAAAAAUUAAAAGUAUAUUUCUAAAAGUUUUCCCCAGAGGCCAGAUACAGUGGCUCAUGCCUAUAAUCCCAGCACUUUGGGAGCCUGAGAUAGGAGUAUUGCUUGAGGCUAGGAGUUUGAGACCAACCUGGCAACAUGGCAAGACCCUAUCUCUACAAAAAUUUUAAAACUUAGCCAGGUGUGGUAGUGCACCUGUAGUCCCAGCUAGUCAGUAGGCUGAGGUGGGAGUAUUGCUUGAGGCUGCAGUGAGGUGUGAUCACGCCACUGCACUCCGGCCUGACAGAAUGAGAUCCUGUCUCAAAAAGAAAAUUCCCCAGAAGAAGAAUUCUAAUUUUAUCAAGCUGAAUUAAAGUUUGAGAGUCUUUUUUUUAAAAUCUUACUGUGUCAAAAGAGGCAUUAUGUUGCUUGUGUGAUAUAGUGAAUAGUGUCCCUCCAAAUUUCAUGUACACCUGGAAUGUCACAAUGUGACUUAACAGUAGCCACCCCUCACCCCCGCCCUUAUCUGUGGUGGAUACAUUUGCAAGAUCCCCAGUGGAUGCCUGAAACCGCAGAUAGUACUGAACCUUAUAUAUACUGUUUGUUUUCCUAUGCAUACAUAUCCCUAUGAUAAAGUUUAUGAAUUUGGCACUUAACAGCAGAACUAAUAAGAUGAAAGAGUUGUAACAAUAUACUCUAAUAAAAGUUAUUUAAAAUGUA